GCAUUGGCGCGGGGAGGAGCAGGGAUCUUGGCAGCGGGCGAGGAGGCUGCGAGCGAGCCGCGAACCGAGCGGGCGGCGGGCGCGCGCACCAUGGGGGAGAAACCCGGGACCAGGGUCUUCAAGAAGUCGAGCCCUAACUGCAAGCUCACCGUGUACUUGGGCAAGCGGGACUUCGUAGAUCACCUGGACAAAGUGGACCCUGUAGAUGGCGUGGUGCUUGUGGACCCUGACUACCUGAAGGACCGCAAAGUGUUUGUGACCCUCACCUGCGCCUUCCGCUAUGGCCGUGAAGACCUGGAUGUGCUGGGCUUGUCCUUCCGCAAAGACCUGUUCAUCGCCACCUACCAGGCCUUCCCCCCGGUGCCCAACCCACCCCGGCCCCCCACCCGCCUGCAGGACCGGCUGCUGAGGAAGCUGGGCCAGCAUGCCCACCCCUUCUUCUUCACCGUGAGGAUGCCCCUGCCCUCUGAGGGCCAGGGGGCUGGGGCUGGGACUGUGUCUGGGGUGGGGAUACCCCAGAAUCUUCCAUGCUCCGUCACACUGCAGCCAGGCCCAGAGGAUACAGGAAAGGCCUGCGGCGUAGACUUUGAGAUUCGAGCCUUCUGUGCUAAAUCACUAGAAGAGAAAAGCCACAAAAGGAACUCUGUGCGGCUGGUGAUCCGAAAGGUGCAGUUCGCCCCGGAGAAACCCGGCCCCCAGCCUUCAGCCGAAACCACACGCCACUUCCUCAUGUCUGACCGGUCCCUGCACCUCGAGGCUUCCCUGGACAAGGAGCUGUACUACCAUGGGGAGCCCCUCAAUGUAAAUGUCCACGUCACCAACAACUCCACCAAGACCGUCAAGAAGAUCAAAGUCUCUGUGAGACAGUACGCCGACAUCUGCCUCUUCAGCACCGCCCAGUACAAGUGUCCUGUGGCUCAACUCGAACAAGAUGACCAGGUAUCUCCCAGCUCCACAUUCUGUAAGGUGUACACCAUAACCCCACUGCUCAGCGACAACCGGGAGAAGCGGGGUCUCGCCCUGGAUGGGAAACUCAAGCACGAGGACACCAACCUGGCUUCCAGCACCAUCGUGAAGGAGGGUGCCAACAAGGAGGUGCUGGGAAUCCUGGUGUCCUACAGGGUCAAGGUGAAGCUGGUGGUGUCUCGAGGCGGGGAUGUCUCUGUGGAGCUGCCUUUUGUUCUUAUGCACCCCAAGCCCCACGACCACAUCCCCCUCCCCAGACCCCAGUCAGCCGCUCCGGAGACAGAUGUCCCUGUGGACACCAACCUCAUUGAAUUUGAUACCAACUAUGCCACAGAUGAUGACAUUGUGUUUGAGGACUUUGCCCGGCUUCGGCUGAAGGGGAUGAAGGAUGACGACUAUGAUGAUCAACUCUGCUAGGAAGCGGGGUGGGAAGAAGGGAGGGGAUGGGGUUGGGAGAGGUGAGGGCAGGAUUAAGAUCCCCACUGUCAAUGGGGGAUUGUCCCAGCCCCUCUUCCCUUCCCCUCACCUGGAAGCUUCUUCAACCAAUCCCUUCACACUCUCUCCCCCAUCCCCCCAAGAUACACACUGGACCCUCUCUUGCUGAAUGUGGGCAUUAAUUUUUUGACUGCAGCUCUGCUUCUCCAGCCCCGCCGUGGGUGGCAAGCUGUGUUCAUACCUAAAUUUUCUGGAAGGGGACAGUGAAAAGAGGAGUGACAGGAGGGAAAGGGGGAGACAAAACUCCUACUCUCAACCUCACACCAACACCUCCCAUUAUCACUCUCUCUGCCCCCAUUCCUUCAAGAGGAGACCCUUUGGGGACAAGGCCGUUUCUUUGUUUCUGAGCAUAAAGAAGAAAAUAAAUCUUUUACUAAGCA